GCGUAAACUCCGCUGGAGCGCGGCGGCAGAGCAGGUGAGCGGGCGGUGCCGGGGGGUGCCCAGGCCAGGGCCCUGUCGCCUGCGGCGCUGAGGGCCCGGGGUGGGGCUGCGCCCUGAGGGCCCUGCCCUGCCCUCCGCACGCCUCUGGCCACGGUCCCUUCCCCGGCUGUGGGUCUGCGGCCCCUGCGUGCGCAGCGCUCCUGGCCUCUGCGGCCAGCGCGGGGGCGGAGAGAGGAGAGUGCCCGGCAGGCGGCGGCUGGGCCGGCCCGGAACUGGGUCGUGGAAGGAUCGCGGGGAGCGGCCCUCAGGCCUUCGGCCUCACUGCGUCCCCACUUCCCUGCGCCCGCCUGCCGCCGAGCCCCGGCUGGGGGUGGGCGCGGCGCGAGCGGUUAAAGGGCCGGUGCAUUUAAAGGAGCGGUGCACGUGGGUCUCUGAGGCGUGUAGCAGGCGGGGGCGUUUUGUUCUUCUUCUCUCUCGCCGGAGACCUCCGUUGCGCCGAGUCCAUUCGGCCUCUAGCACCGGGUCCUGGGCAUGCUUUCCCCGGGAAGGAGGCGCGCGGGGGCUCUGCCCGCACGUGAGGGGCAGGGCCGCAGGCUCAAGCCUAGAGCCGGUUUCUGUUAGCAGCGGUGUUUGGCUGUUUUAUCAGGCAUUUCCAGCAGUGAGGAGACAGCCAGAAGCAAGCUUUUGGAGCUGAAGGAACCUGAGACAGAAGCUAGUCCCCCCUCUGAAUUUUACUGAUGAAGAAACUGAGGCCACAGAGCUAAAGUGACUUUUCCCAAGGUCGCCCAGCGAGGACGUGGGACUUCUCAGACGUCAGGAGAGUGAUGUGAGGGAGCUGUGUGACCAUAGAAAGUGACGUGUUAAAAACCAGCGCUGCCCUCUUUGAAAGCCAGGGAGCAUCAUUCAUUUAGCCUGCUGAGAAGAAGAAACCAAGUGUCCGGGAUUCAGACCUCUCUGCGGCCCCAAGUGUUCGUGGGUGUGAAGCUCAGCCCUGAGGGUCUCUGGACAGCGAUCACUCAGCCUCUGGACAGCGAUCACUCAGCCUCUGGACAGACAGCGAUCACUCAGCCUCUGGACAGCGAUCACUCAGCCUCUGGACAGCGAUCACUCAGCCUCUGGACAGCGAUAACUCAGCCUCUGUCCCCGUCUGAGAUGUUGGCAGGGACUGUCAGAUUUGCCAGGCAUUGUUUGAAGUUCUUCCCAGCCCAGAAACCUGCAUGUGUAGAUUUUGGUACACUGGGUCCCCCACUUGGUACUACUGUGUGAAACCCCACUUGGCACUGUUUUAGGGGGCAGGCUUCCCUCCUGUCCCCUUGGCCUUGGCCUUCCCCUGGGUCCCGCCCUCAGUGGCACUUCCCCACCUCACACGUCUGCUCUCAUGGCUUAGGUCUCCACUUCUAACCUCAGGAGACCUGGUCCUCAGACACCUCCCAGACAGCUUCCCCAUUUUAUCCCAUAGACACUCAAAGGGUGAAAUUCAUGGUCUUUCCCGAGACUCUCUUCUCCGGUCUUCCCUGUCUUAGUCCCCACCUGGCUGCCAUUCUAGACUGUGUUUUCUCUCCUGCGUCAGGUCCUGCCCUUGACCUCUUGACCCCUUCUGGACUCUGCCCUCACUUGCAUCCAUCCUGCUGCUGUCCUCAGCUCUCCUCACCUGCCACAGUUGUCUCUGGGGGUCACUUUCCCUCUCUGGUCAGUGGCCAGACUGACUUUUAUAAACCUGGUUCAGAUCUUGUCUGUCAAGAUUGUCCUCAGGGUGAUGUGUGUCUCCUUAACAUGGUGCCUGAGACCCUGAUCAUCUCCACUGCCCGCCCCACAGUGUGAGGCCCUCACUGGAACAUUGUGCCUUCUGCCCUUCCCUCCUCCUGGGAAAACCAGUCUCCAUCAGAUAGGCUCUUCUCUAGAAAACAUUCGUGAUCUCUGAGAUUUGGUUCCACUUUUGUGCUUCUGCACCUACCAUCAAACACCCGGAUUGUAUCAUUUGUCACAUUAGAUGAUUUUUGUUUUGUUUUAAGACAAGGGUGUUUCUUACUCAUCUUUUUAUCCCCAGAGCCCAGCAUGAUCUUUGGUGCAUAAUAGAUGCACCACAGAUGUUUGCUGAUUGAAUGAAUGAGCACACUGACAGUUUGGAGCUGCCCUGACUUUCGUGGCUAUGCGUUUUGCCCCCUGGGAUGUGAGUCACCUCAGGCCAGCCCCAGGCAAGGCCGCUGCUGCCUCCAUGGUAACUCUCAAGGCCUCUUGUUUUAUGGCAGUCGUUUGAUUGACAGGCAUCUCUUGGAAGCUUUUGGGGCAGGACUUGUGUCCAAGUCUCCAGGUCGCCUCCAGCCACCCCCUGAGUCCUCCACUGCCUUUGUCUCACAGGAAAGUGGAACAAGGUCCUUGUGCUCCUUUUUCCAGGUGCUUCCAGAGGCAGGGCUAUGCUCACAUUCAUGGCCUCUGACAGCGAGGAAGAAGUGUGUGAUGAGCGGACGUCCCUAAUGUCGGCUGAGAGCCCCACGCCGCGCUCCUGCCAGGAGGGCAGGCAGGGCCCAGAGGAUGGAGAGAACACUGCCCAGUGGAGAAGCCAGGAGAACGAGGAGGACGGUGAGGAGGACCCUGACCGCUAUGUCUGUAGUGGGGUUCCCGGGCGGCCGCCAGGCCUGGAGGAAGAGCUGACCCUCAAAUACGGAGCGAAGCACGUGAUCAUGCUGUUUGUGCCUGUCACUCUGUGCAUGAUCGUGGUGGUAGCCACCAUCAAGUCUGUGCGCUUCUACACAGAGAAGAAUGGACAGCUCAUCUACACGCCAUUCACUGAGGACACACCCUCGGUGGGCCAGCGCCUCCUCAACUCCGUGCUGAACACCCUCAUCAUGAUCAGCGUCAUCGUGGUUAUGACCAUCUUCUUGGUGGUGCUCUACAAGUACCGCUGCUACAAGUUCAUCCAUGGCUGGUUGAUCAUGUCUUCACUGAUGCUGCUGUUCCUCUUCACCUAUAUCUACCUUGGGGAAGUGCUCAAGACCUACAAUGUGGCCAUGGACUACCCCACCCUCUUGCUGACUGUCUGGAACUUCGGGGCAGUGGGCAUGGUGUGCAUCCACUGGAAGGGCCCUCUGGUGCUGCAGCAGGCCUACCUCAUCAUGAUCAGUGCGCUCAUGGCCCUAGUGUUCAUCAAGUACCUCCCAGAGUGGUCCGCGUGGGUCAUCCUGGGCGCCAUCUCUGUGUAUGAUCUCGUGGCUGUGCUGUGUCCCAAAGGGCCUCUGAGAAUGCUGGUAGAAACUGCCCAGGAGAGAAAUGAGCCCAUAUUCCCUGCCCUGAUAUACUCAUCUGCCAUGGUGUGGACGGUUGGCAUGGCGAAGCUGGACCCCUCCUCUCAGGGUGCCCUCCAGCUCCCCUACGACCCGGAGAUGGAAGACUCCUAUGACAGUUUUGGGGAGCCUUCAUACCCCGAAGUCUUUGAGCCUCCCUUGACUGGCUACCCAGGGGAGGAGCUGGAGGAAGAGGAGGAAAGGGGCGUGAAGCUUGGCCUCGGGGACUUCAUCUUCUACAGUGUGCUGGUGGGCAAGGCGGCUGCCACGGGCAGCGGGGACUGGAAUACCACGCUGGCCUGCUUCGUGGCCAUCCUCAUUGGCUUGUGUCUGACCCUCCUGCUGCUUGCUGUGUUCAAGAAGGCGCUGCCCGCCCUCCCCAUCUCCAUCACGUUCGGGCUCAUCUUUUACUUCUCCACGGACAACCUGGUGCGGCCGUUCAUGGACACCCUGGCCUCCCAUCAGCUCUACAUCUGAGGGACAUGGUGUGCCACAGGCUGCAAGCUGCAGGGAAUUUUCAUUGGAUGCAGUUGUAUAGUUUUACACUCUAGUGCCAUAUAUUUUUAAGACUUUUCUUUCCUUAAAAAAUAAAGUACGUGUUUACUUGGUGAGGAGGAGGCAGAACCAGCUCUUUGGUGCCAGCUGUUUCAUCACCAGACUUUGGCUCCCGCUUUGGGGAGCGCCUCGCUUCACGGACAGGAAGCACAGCAGGUUUAUCCAGAUGAACUGAGAAGGUCAGAUUAGGGCGGGGAGAAGAGCAUCCGGCAUGAGGGCUGAGAUGCGCAAAGAGUGUGCUCGGGAGUGGCCCCUGGCACCUGGGUGCUCUGGCUGGAGAGGAAAAGCCAGUUCCCUACGAGGAGUGUUCCCAAUGCUUUGUCCAUGAUGUCCUUGUUAUUUUAUUGCCUUUAGAAACUGAGUCCUGUUCUUGUUACGGCAGUCACACUGCUGGGAAGUGGCUUAAUAGUAAUAUCAAUAAAUAGAUGAGUCCUGUUAGAA